GGGGUCCUGCGGAGUUGGCGGAGGCGGCGGAGGCUCCUCCAGGGACUGGGGCACCGAUCUGCGUAGAAACGGGUGGCGGGGAAGAGAGGGGAGGAGAGCUCUGAGUGGGAAGCGGAACCGGGGGCCUGGGACCCGUCGCGUCAGAGCCAGGCAAGUGAACCGGAGCAAACGACUUCCGAUCCAGUCUGCGCUGUUGCGGCUCCCGUUUGGGAUUUGAUUUGCAGCAUCUUUGAGCCUCUACGACAAAAAACCGCGAAGCACGCCCAGCCCUCCCCCGGCACCCCGAAAAGCACCCACUCCCUCCCGGGGACACAGCUGGGCGCGUCCACACCCCCGCAGCCCCACACCAUGUUGUGCGGAAGGACUUCCACUCCCCGCCUGUGUCGUUGAUGUCAGACCCCAGGCCAGCCUCCGGGCGCUGCAGUUCUCCCGGCUAAUGCUGAGGCUGCGGCUCCGGCUCUAGCACAGGCACCAGCCGCCGCCGCACCCGGCCUCAGCGCCCACCGUCUGCAUGUGCCCGCCGUAGCCGUCUGCCCAGCCCGCAGCCCGCGCUCCACGGAGCGCUGGAGACCACCGUGGGGGGCCCCUUCUGCCCUCGAGAGAAGCGGUCUUGGAGGUAUUGAUUUAGGUGGUUGGAUUUUUUCCGUGGAUCUAUCAAUUCACAAUUCGAAUUUGGAAGAAAGAAGGAAAACAUGACGUCUCCAGCCAAAUUCAAAAAGGAUAAGGAGAUCAUAGCAGAGUACGAUACUCAGGUCAAAGAGAUCCGUGCUCAGCUCACAGAGCAGAUGAAAUGCCUGGACCAGCAGUGUGAGCUUCGGGUGCAACUGUUGCAGGACCUCCAGGACUUCUUCCGAAAGAAGGCAGAGAUUGAGAUGGACUACUCCCGCAACCUGGAGAAGCUGGCAGAACACUUCCUGGCCAAGACACGCAGCACCAAGGACCAGCAAUUCAAGAAGGAUCAGAAUGUUCUCUCUCCAGUCAACUGCUGGAAUCUCCUCUUAAACCAGGUGAAGUGGGAAAGCAGGGACCAUACCACCCUGAGUGACAUCUACCUGAAUAAUAUCAUUCCUCGAUUUGUACAAGUCAGCGAGGACUCAGGAAGACUCUUUAAAAAGAGUAAAGAAGUCGGCCAGCAGCUCCAAGAUGAUUUGAUGAAGGUCCUGAACGAGCUCUACUCGGUCAUGAAGACAUAUCACAUGUACAAUGCCGACAGCAUCAGUGCUCAGAGCAAACUAAAGGAGGCGGAGAAGCAGGAGGAGAAGCAAAUUGGUAAAUCGGUAAAGCAGGAGGACCGGCAGACCCCAUGCUCCCCUGACUCCACGGCCAACGUUCGCAUUGAGGAGAAACAUGUCCGGAGGAGCUCAGUGAAGAAGAUUGAGAAGAUGAAGGAGAAGCACCAAGCCAAGUACACGGAGAAUAAGCUGAAGGCCAUCAAAGCCCAGAAUGAGUACUUGCUGGCUUUGGAGGCAACCAAUGCAUCUGUCUUCAAGUACUACAUCCAUGACCUAUCUGACCUUAUUGAUCAGUGUUGUGACUUAGGCUACCAUGCAAGUCUGAACCGGGCUCUACGCACCUUCCUCUCUGCUGAGUUAAACCUGGAACAGUCGAAGCAUGAGGGUCUGGAUGCCAUCGAGAAUGCAGUAGAAAACCUGGAUGCCACCAGUGACAAGCAGCGCCUCAUGGAGAUGUACAACAACGUCUUCUGCCCCCCUAUGAAGUUUGAGUUUCAGCCCCACAUGGGGGAUAUGGCUUCCCAGCUCUGUGCCCAGCAGCCUGUCCAGAGUGAGCUGGUACAGAGAUGCCAACAACUGCAGUCUCGCUUAUCCACUCUAAAGAUUGAAAACGAAGAGGUAAAGAAGACAAUGGAGGCCACCCUGCAAACCAUCCAGGACAUUGUGACUGUCGAGGACUUUGAUGUGUCUGACUGCUUCCAGUACAGCAACUCCAUGGAGUCCGUCAAGUCCACGGUCUCUGAAACCUUCAUGAGCAAGCCCAGCAUUGCUAAGAGGAGAGCCAACCAGCAAGAGACAGAGCAGUUUUAUUUCACAGUAAGGGAGUGCUAUGGCUUUUAAAGAGCGUCAGCAUGCACUGCAGCACUCAAGGGAGAUUUGGAACUCAGAGUCCUUGUUAAGUGUCUGAAGGACAGGCAUUGAAUAUCUUAGAUACGAAUGUGGGCAUACUCAGAGACCAUCCCUACACUUAAAGGUGCAAACAUUAAAAGUUGUAUAUGUCUAACAGGGAUCCGCCCAAGAGAAAGGAUGCUCCCAAGUAUACAACUAAGAAGAUUUUCUUUUUUAAGAAAUUUUUAACUAGCUAGUAGGCUUUCACUGGAAAGUUUCCUUCUCAGGCACAGGGGAUCCUGAAAGGGGAACUUCAUCUUUUAGUUCUUGGAGAGUACAUACAAAUAUUCAUAAUAACACAUAUUUUGUUUAUAAAAAUCUAUAAUCUCUUCUAGGUGAUAUGAUGACAUUAUUUUAUAACUUUUAUUGUUGGGAAACUAUUUUUUCUAAUUAUUGCUAAAACUUAAAGGAUGGGUAAUAUGCAGCAUUACUAUUUUGCACAUAAUUCCAAAACAUCGUAUUUUCUUAUUCAUGUAUCUCUAGUCUUCUUUUAGACAGUUGGACCCUUUUUUCUUUUUCUUUUUUUUUUUUUUUUUUUAAGUAUUGUUAACAAUCCUUUGGAAGUCACUACUGGUCUUUGUGUGCUGCUUUUUAAUAAUUGAGUUAUUUUGAGCUUGCCAAGUAGGAUCUAUUGCCUGGACUAAAAUUUAUUUCCUAAUCUUCUGAUGACCAAGAAAGGAAAAAUUAAGUUUGCAGAUGUGAGAUGAAAUAUAGCCAGUGAAUAUGCAUACUGAUUCUGAAUGAAAGGAAUUAACUUUUCAGUCAAGAAACAGUCUGCAUGCAGUAAAUUGAAUUUUUCCUGCAACUGGAAUGAUUUGUUUAAUUCUUCUUUGAACACUGCCCUUUCUCCAGUAAGAACACUAAUGAUUUGCUAAUAUUUUUUAAAGAAAUCUGUUUUUUUAAUUAGUUAAGCUCAGACUUCCUCUUAUUUUUUAUCCUAGAGAAAACUGCUAAAAGGGAAUGAUAUAUCAGUACUAUUCUUCUAAAACAACUUUUUAAAAAUGAUUAUACAAAGCCAAAUAUGCUCAUUAUAUAAAAUUUAGAAGCAAAAAGAAGGAAAUAAAAAUUUUCCAUAAUUCUACCAGCUAGAGAUAAUGGUGUUAGAAUAUAUUCCUUUCUAAUCUGUUUUCUAUGCAUGCACAAACACAUAUGUGAGCACAUAUUUAUAAUUUUAUUCUAAAAAAUAGGACACUGCUGUACAUAUUGUUUUACAAUCUAAGUCAUAUAAUUAUAAUAUUCUUUAAGCAUAUUUAUGAGUAAAAUAUUAAAACCUAUACAAAAAAAUAACAGAAUGGCAUUUUAGCUCAUUCAUUGAUUUUUAUAAAAUAUUUAACACACUCCCUGGUUUGUAGUUAGCGUUCAAUAAAUGCUAAAAAUUUAUCUUCACCAUCAUCAUUAAUUUAUUUAUUAAUCAUUAUUAAAUUAUUCAUUGAUCAUUUUUUGAGGAUUUACUAUUGCCAGACACUGUGCUACAAGCUGGGAAUGCUGACAGUAUAAGAUAAAGAGGGAAAUGAUGGGGGAUGGGUCAUGUAAAGGGAGAACUUUCAUUUUUACUUCAUAUAUAUCUAAGCAGUUAUAAUAGGUUGAUUUUUGUAAUUUAAAAAAUGUAAAAAUGCAUACAUGCACUAGUGCAUGAAUGGCAGCCAGGAUGAGUGGAAUUGGAGAAGCAUCACACACACAGUGACUUUUGUGUUUGAUCUUGAAGAAUGAGCGAACCAGGCAGGGAGUCGGGGAGGAGAAUCGCAUUCCUUGAGGAAAGAGCAGCAUGUGGGAAAACAUAAAUGCACGCAAUAACCUGGCUCACAUGUUAAGAGAACUUUCUGACUAUAAUGAGGGAUGUGUUGCUGCCCCAAGCUUCAUUAUCUAAGGAGUUUGUUGAACACUCUCUAGAGGCUUUUAAUAAUAGGAUUGUUUAGCUGGUCUGUCUGGACUGGUUAGAUAUAACACUAUUUAAAUGACCCAAUCUCAUUACAUUGUGAAGAUUUCCAUUUUUUAGGUUACGUAAGAAAUUUUGGACCUAAAAAUCUUGCAUUUUAAGACAGUCUUUGUCAGAAUUACUUUUUGGCUCUAAAUGAAUUCUGUAACAUUUGUAUUCUAAAUUGACCUUUAGUAAAAGCAGGAAUGGCCAUAUUCAAACUGGUAACCUCGCAAAUCCUGCCCACCCUUUCACUUUCUGUCUCAAUACAUUGAUGUCCUCUAACCCAUUUCCUGUCUUAUGUGGCUUUAGUGCCACUUAUCAAAAUUGUGUGCAAAUUUCCUUGGCUAACAGUAACAGUUUUUGUCUGGGCUUGUCUAGCAGUGGAAUUCUGCCUGAGUUCAUCAUUUUUGUGACUGGUACUUGAAGUGCAUCAGAUGAUUAAUUUCAUGAUAAGAGGGCUUUUUGGGGUGGUGAAAUAGACAUUUAUGGAAAAUGGGAUACCCACAUUAAGCAGGGUGACUACCUGUUUACCAUACAACCCACACAAAGCCAAUACAACUAUAGAUGUGCUUUCUUUAGUCUGUUGCCUCUGCAAACAUUGCCCGUGUGUUUCUCUAUGCCCUUCAAAAACAUCAGAGCAGCACAUCCUGGAAGAUCCUAUCUUUUGUAAGUUUAAGAAGCAGCCUCUUGUCACAGCUUGACUCCUAGGUAGUGUGCCUAGUGACCAAGAGGGCUGCUAAGAAAGCUUUCUGACCACUUGUGGCUGUCAUUGGACUGAUUUGCCCAGAUGACAUCAAUUGGGAAUUUGAGGCAUGACCUAUAAAGAUCAGUUGCUUGCAAGAGUCUCAGGAAAAUAAUUGUGGAGUUAAGAAACUUGAAGCGAUUUUUAAAAAUUACCUAACCCAACCUUCUCAUUUGAAAAAUUAAAAAAUAAAUAGGCCAGAUAUGGCGGCUCAUGCCUGUAAUCCCAGCGCUGUGGGAGCCUGAGGCGGGUGGGUCUCUUGAGGCCAGGAGUUCAAGACCAGCCUGGACAAUGUGGUGAAACCCUGUCUCUACUAAAAACACAAAAAUUAGCUGGGUGUGGUGGCAGGCGCCUGUAAUCCCAGCUACUCAGGAGGCUAAGGUGGGAGGAUUACUUGAACUGGGGAGGCAUAGGUUGUAGUGAGCCAAGGUCGUGUCACUGCACUCCAGCCUGGGUGACAGAGUAAGACUCUGCCUAAAAAAAAAAAAAGAAAGAUUAAAAAAUAAAUAAAUCUGCUGGGCGUGGUGGCUCACGCCUGUAAUCCCAGCACUUUGGGAGGCCGAGGCGGGUGGAUCACCUGAGGUCGGGAGUUUGAGACCAGCCUGAUCAACAUGGAGAAACCUCGUCUCUACUAAAAACACAAAAAAAUUAGCUGGGCGUGGUGGCGCAUGCCUCAUUCACGUACAUGGGAGAGUCUACAAAGUCACACGUAUUCAUAGGUUAAGCCACAUGCUGACAAAUGUCAUAAGAAGACCCUACACUUUUACCUUGGCCGAUCCCUCCCCUCAGUGCAAGCUCUGUGCAAGAGUGAACUUGAACUUCACUCAGUGCAAGAGUGAACACACACUUUGUGCCGGCUUUAAAGAACCCAGCACAAAGCCAGUCUGCAUGGCCUACAGACAUAUUUUGCUGGACAAUGAUUACUUGCUUUUCUUUUUGUUUUUCUUGUAUAUGCCUGUUUGAUUGGUUCCUGACAUACCAGAAAAUCACUGUCAAAACAUUAGCUUAACAUUUGUUAAGGAAACAAAAAGACUUCGGUGACCACACCUUAUAAACCAAACAGUUUUGUAAAUCACUUUGGAAAAUUUCACUAAAAAAAAAAAUCCUUAACAAUAUAAUAAGUAAAGAAAAUUUAAAACCACAAAACAUUACUGUGUUUGUAGGGGGAGGUCUGAUUUACAGAGUAACCACAUAGUAAUUAUAAUUAUUAGAAUGUCCAGUUUUCAAAAAACGUUACAAGGCAUACAAAGAAUGGGAAAGUGUGGCUCAUUCAAAGGAACAAAAUAAAGUGACAGAAAAUAUCCCUAAGGAAACCCAGACAUCAAACUUACCAGACAAAGACUUUAAAACAACUCUCUUCAUUAUACUCAAAUGUCAAAAGGAAAACAUAAACAAAGAAAUAAAGGAAUCAGAAAAAAUAUUAAAAAGUAGGAAUAUCAGCAAAGAGAUAACAAAUUCUGGAGUGGAAAACUACAAUGAUAAAAAUUUAAAAAUCACCAGAGGGAUUUAAGAGUAUAUUUGCACACACAGAGGAAGCCAUGAACUUGAAGAGAAGAAAAUGGAAAAUACUGUCUCUGAGAAACAGAAAGAAUAAAAAAUAAACAAUGAGCAGAGACUAAUGAAUUUGUGGGACAUCAUCAAAUAGACCAACAUUCAUAUUCUAGAAGGAUAAAUUAUGUUGUUAAAAAGUUUACCAUUCUUUCUUUUCACCUUUCUUCCUUCUUCCUUCCCCCUCCUCCUUUUUACUUUUCUUCCUCUUCCUUUCUCUUCUUCUUUCUCGCCUUCAUUAUCCCUUUCGCUGUUUCUCUUUCUCCCUUUCUCUUUUUUCUUUUCUUUCAAUUUUCUCAAUUACUAAGAGAUGUUUAAGUACCCUUAGCAUGUUAGUAGAUAUGGUUAUUUCUCCCUUUAGUUCUCUUUUGAGAUUUAUAGUCACUCAAAUAAAGAGAUAACCCAAACAUAAGCGUCACAAACAGGCUUUCAUACCAUUCUUAAUUUGGUCCUGUAAUUCUUCAUUGCUGUAUUAAUUUUCUGAUGCUUUUAAGGAUGUUUUAUAACAAAUUGUGUAGCUUUUUCCAAUGGAAUGUUUAUUCUGAAUUAUCUAAUUCAUAUUGUAAGUAUAGAGGGAGUUUAAUAUAAAAUUAUUAAACUAAUAUUUGUGAAAGAAUGUAUUUGAGCAUUUAACAAAUAUGUUAAUCCUCAGACUGUUAUUGGGCAGCUGAGCAUACAGGAAUAAAAAUAACACAAUUUUUAUGUGUACAAUAUUUAUGGAAUACGUUACUGGACCCAAUAAAUAAUUUAGUUAAUAACAUGA